AGAAGCGGAGUGAGUGAGGGAAGCGAUGGGCGCGGGAAUGGCCGGCCCACGGGUCGCAGGAGACGGGACGCCAGUCCUUUGGCUCCGUUCCGCUGGCUCCUUCGUCAGUACUGACACCUCGGGCUUGUAGAGCACUUCACGCAGUGCAAAGCGCCCCCCGUCUAUAUCAUAUCGCCUCUCGGUCCUCCUAAAAGUCGUAUGAGAUGGAGCUGGAGGAGGGGAAGGCAGGCAGCGGACUCCGCCAAUAUUAUCUGUCCAAGAUUGAAGAACUCCAGCUGAUUGUGAAUGAUAAGAGCCAAAACCUCCGGAGGCUGCAGGCACAGAGGAACGAACUAAAUGCUAAAGUUCGCCUAUUGCGGGAGGAGCUACAGCUGCUGCAGGAGCAGGGCUCCUAUGUGGGGGAAGUAGUCCGGGCCAUGGAUAAGAAGAAAGUGUUGGUCAAGGUACAUCCUGAAGGUAAAUUUGUUGUAGACGUGGACAAAAACAUUGACAUCAAUGAUGUGACACCCAAUUGCCGGGUGGCUCUAAGGAAUGACAGCUACACUCUGCACAAGAUCCUGCCCAACAAGGUAGACCCAUUAGUGUCACUGAUGAUGGUGGAGAAAGUACCAGAUUCAACUUAUGAGAUGAUUGGUGGACUGGACAAACAGAUCAAGGAGAUCAAAGAAGUGAUCGAGCUGCCUGUUAAGCAUCCUGAGCUCUUCGAAGCACUGGGCAUUGCUCAGCCCAAGGGAGUGCUGCUGUAUGGACCUCCAGGCACUGGGAAGACACUGUUGGCCCGGGCUGUGGCUCAUCAUACGGACUGUACCUUUAUUCGUGUCUCUGGCUCUGAACUGGUACAGAAAUUCAUAGGGGAAGGGGCAAGAAUGGUGAGGGAGCUGUUUGUCAUGGCACGGGAACAUGCUCCAUCUAUCAUCUUCAUGGACGAAAUCGACUCCAUCGGCUCCUCGCGGCUGGAGGGGGGUUCUGGAGGGGACAGUGAAGUGCAGCGCACGAUGCUGGAGUUGCUCAACCAGCUCGACGGCUUUGAGGCCACCAAGAACAUCAAGGUUAUCAUGGCUACUAAUAGGAUUGAUAUCCUGGACUCGGCACUGCUUCGCCCAGGGCGCAUUGACAGAAAAAUUGAAUUCCCACCCCCCAAUGAGGAGGCCCGGCUGGACAUUUUGAAGAUUCAUUCUCGGAAGAUGAACCUGACCCGGGGGAUCAACCUGAGAAAAAUUGCUGAGCUCAUGCCAGGAGCAUCAGGGGCUGAAGUGAAGGGCGUGUGCACAGAAGCUGGCAUGUAUGCCCUGCGAGAACGGCGAGUCCAUGUCACUCAGGAGGACUUUGAGAUGGCAGUAGCCAAGGUCAUGCAGAAGGACAGUGAGAAAAACAUGUCCAUCAAGAAAUUAUGGAAGUGAGUGGACAGCCUUUGUGUGUAUCUCUCCAAUAAAGCUCUGUGGGCCAAGUC